ACAACUCGCGGCUCUAGGGAAGGCCACAGACCUCAGCUGUACGAGCGGAACCUGGACUAGAGGAACUUUCCUCAGGACUCAGGGCACACAGCCCCUCGGCCACUACUGUCUGCGAGCCCGAGGCGCAGGGGAGCGCCAGCGGCUGCAGGUACGCUGCGCACCCGCACUGGGGCCUGGGCGGUGCAGCGGCGGCGGGAGGGUCCUGGGAACCGCAGCCGCCGAGGCCAGUGUGUGAGCCGGCCGGCCGCGGCAAGCCGCAUCCCCCGGCCGCCCCUCGCAGCCCCUUGCUCCCCGGCAGCCGCCGCCGCCCUCAGGCAGCCCAGCCGGGCGCUCGCGCCAGGACUUCCCCGCCGCCCGCCUCGGCCCGGAACAUGGCUGCGCGCCCUGCUGCCACCCUCGCCUGGUCGCUACUGCUCCUCUCCUCAGCCCUGCUCCGCGAAGGCUGCCGAGCGCGCUUCGUCGCCGAGCGGGACUCGGAGGACGACGGAGAGGAGCCGGUGGUUUUCCCGGAGUCGCCCCUGCAGAGCCCCACGGUGCUCGUGGCGGUCCUCGCCCGCAACGCGGCGCACACGCUGCCGCACUUCCUCGGCUGCCUGGAGCGGCUGGACUACCCCAAGAGCAGGAUGGCCAUCUGGGCAGCCACUGAUCACAAUGUGGAUAAUACAACAGAAAUAUUCAGGGAGUGGUUGAAAAAUGUACAGAGACUCUAUCACUAUGUGGAGUGGAGGCCUAUGGAUGAACCAGAGUCUUACCCUGAUGAAAUUGGACCAAAGCACUGGCCAACCUCCCGGUUUGCCCAUGUGAUGAAACUACGACAGGCAGCCCUUCGAACUGCGAGGGAAAAAUGGUCAGACUACAUUCUGUUCAUAGAUGUUGACAAUUUCCUGACUAAUCCACAGACCCUCAAUCUACUGAUUGCAGAAAACAAAACUAUUGUGGCCCCCAUGCUGGAGUCUCGGGGCCUGUAUUCUAAUUUCUGGUGCGGAAUCACCCCUAAGGGCUUCUAUAAGAGGACCCCAGACUACGUUCAGAUUCGAGAAUGGAAGAGGACAGGCUGCUUCCCCGUCCCCAUGGUCCACUCCACCUUCCUAAUUGACCUCAGGAAGGAGGCCUCGGACAAGCUGACUUUCUACCCCCCACACCAGGACUACACCUGGACCUUUGAUGACAUCAUUGUCUUUGCCUUCUCCAGCAGGCAAGCAGGCAUCCAGAUGUACCUCUGCAACAGAGAGCACUAUGGCUACCUGCCCAUCCCCCUGAAGCCCCAUCAGACACUGCAGGAAGACAUCGAGAACCUCAUCCAUGUGCAGAUUGAAGCAAUGAUUGACCGUCCUCCAAUGGAACCCUCCCAGUAUGUCUCAGUUGUCCCUAAAUAUCCAGACAAGAUGGGAUUUGAUGAGAUUUUCAUGAUAAACCUCAAACGCAGAAAGGACAGGCGGGACCGGAUGCUGCGCACACUGUAUGAACAGGAGAUUGAGGUCAAGAUUGUCGAGGCUGUGGAUGGAAAGGCACUCAACACAAGCCAGCUGAAGGCACUGAAUAUUGAAAUGCUGCCUGGCUAUCGAGAUCCCUAUUCCUCCAGGCCUCUAACAAGGGGUGAAAUCGGCUGCUUUCUCAGCCACUACUCAGUCUGGAAAGAGGUAAUUGAUCGAGAGCUAGAGAAGACUCUUGUAAUUGAAGACGAUGUGCGUUUUGAGCAUCAGUUUAAGAAGAAGCUGAUGAAGCUGAUGGAUAACAUUGACCAGGCUCAGCUGGACUGGGAACUGAUUUAUAUUGGUAGGAAGAGGAUGCAAGUAAAGGAGCCAGAGAAAGCAGUGCCCAAUGUGGCAAACCUGGUCGAAGCCGACUAUUCCUACUGGACCCUGGGCUACGUCAUCUCUCUGGAAGGAGCACAGAAGCUGGUUGGAGCCAAUCCUUUUGGGAAGAUGCUGCCAGUGGAUGAGUUUCUGCCAGUCAUGUACAACAAGCAUCCCGUAGCCGAGUACAAGGAGUAUUAUGAAUCCAGGGACCUGAAAGCCUUCUCUGCAGAACCCUUGCUCAUCUACCCUACGCACUACACAGGCCAGCCGGGGUACCUGAGUGACACGGAGACCUCCACCAUCUGGGACAAUGAGACAGUGGCCACCGACUGGGAUAGGACACAUGCCUGGAAGUCCCGGAAGCAAAGCCGCAUCUACAGCAAUGCCAAGAACACAGAGGCCCUGCCACCGCCAACCUCCCUGGACACUGUGCCUUCAAGGGAUGAGCUAUGAAGGCUCCCUGGGAGUGUGGCCCACAUCAGUUCAACAUCCUCUGGUUUUUCUAAAGGGCUAUUCAUCUGUUUGCUCCAGUUUUCUGUUUUGUUUUGUUCUUAGUGGUCACAGUCAUCUAACCAAAGUGAUCUAGUGUGAUAGAUCGAAAUUAACAUAUUUUUGACCAUGGAAGGAAAUAAGGAAAUUCAACCCAAAUUUCCCAAGACGGCUGAAAGACAGGUUUUUUGGAAACUGUUAAGAUAAACUGUAAUCCAGACACCUAAUUCUUCAGUUCACUACUCAUGUGAUACUGAUUCCCACAUUAAGGUUGAACAACAUGGCUCAGAGUCUUGUUCAAGAGAAAGUGAUCACCGAGCUGUCACAUCAGCAAAUAUGUAGUCAAGGCAGCCAGGCCAACUAGACCACACUUAUUGGUCUAGUUUGUCCGUUUUAUAUGACAUUGAAAACUUGUGUGUGCAACUUUUGGGGGACAGGAAUCACUUAAAAUCAUAUUUAUUUGGCUUUUUAUUUAAAGGAUUCUGUCACAAGUCUUAUUGAAAAGUAGAUUUUUUAAAAAAAAAAAAUCUUAGUCCCUGUUAUCCAGUAGGGGUGGGUAUUUGGGUCCGACUGAGACUUGGCCUGUGACCAUCAUGGCAGUUGGAGUUCUCAUAUAGAGGUGACCAGUUUGCCAUGUGGAUAUAAUUUAGUAGAUAUUUGACAGUUUGUGUAGGUAUUUGAGGGAAAAAACUCAAUGUUUGGCUUUUUUAUUAUGGCCACUCGAGUCAGGAUGCUCUAUUUAUAAAGAUAAAUGUAAUAUAUAAAGGGUGAGGACUGGCUGUGCAUCCUGCCCUGUCCCGGGUUUGCGCGCUGCUACAGAGCUUCACGCUCUCCGCUCCACCCCUUAGCCUGGGAACCCACCGCAGGUGUGAGUUCUGUGAGUCACUGCUAAGAGACAGAGCACAUUUUCAGGCCAGCAACUAUCCUUGCCAGAGUUUUUUCAUUAUAUUUUGAAUUAUUUAUUUUACAAAAUGGGCGAAGAUAUUGUCUUUAGGAUAAGGCAGAGAAACAGAUGUUGCAGACUUCCACGGCACCCGGGGGAGUGGUGGGUGUGGACACAUUGGUUCGGCAAUCUGAUUCUCCUGAAUUUCCCAGCCAGGCUCUUGUGGGGAGGCCUGUGGAUGGGGGGAUUUGAACUAUUUGGAAACAAAUGAUUCUCUAUCUCAGGUGAGAAACCUGGUCAGAAACAAAGGGCUGGUCACCUGAUUUAGGCCAGCAACCAGGGAAGCUCUUAGAAUCCCAGGCGGACACCCUUUCUCAAAAGAUAUCCCCUAAGAGUCCUUUCUGCUUUCUUCACAGAUUGAUUUUAUGUAAAAUGCAGAGUUGGACUACACGAUUUCUUCCCACUCCACAAUCUGUCAUCCUAGUAUAGAUCAUGGUGGUUUCCCUCAAGUUUAUGUUCUCAUGCCCUCAAUCUGUAAAUUUUUGUCUCCAGAAAAACCCUCCCAGGCAUCCCAUACCAGCACCGUUCCUCAUCACUGUCCAUGCACCAUGCAGCCAUAUGGGGGGCCGUGCACACCCCAAACCCUGAGCUUCACACUUAAACUCAUGGGGAGGGCCCUUCAGAGCAGAGUCCACAGGCGGGUGGUGCUACAUACACAAGCUUAGUGUACGAGUGUAAGAUACACUUUAAGCCAGACACCUAAUUCUUCAGUUCACUGCCCAUGUGAUACUGAUUGCCACAUUAAGGUUGAACAGCAUGGCUCAGAGUCUAGAGAAAGUGAUCACCAAGCUGUCUCAUCACCAAAUAGGUAGUCAAGGCAGCCUCAUCUCCCCAGGUGAGGGGCGGGUCCCCACUUUAGGACAAGAGGCAGCUUGCCUUCCACCAGACGCCAGCCUCGGCCUUCCUUCCCGACUCACUGUGGGUACCCUUCUACACUGACCAGCAAGCUAGGCCGCUGGAGGAAAGGGAACUCACCCAACUCUAAAUUGUGCCGCUUAGACUUAGCUGUCAGUGUGACUUCCUUUCCCACCCACCCCCAGAAAAACAGAAAGAGCAUCUGGGGAGCGAGUGAAAAUUCCUUAGGUGAUUCCUAAGAUUUCCUUGGGUAUCUGGUUUUUGUUUUCAUAUUUGAGUGUGUGCAUGUGUGCAUGACUUUAAUGACUUUUUUAAUGGGGUGGGAGGUGGCUGGGGUGCUGGGGUUGAAGGAAGUUUGGGUUGAUUUUUGUGGUGUUUUGUUUAAUAGAGAAUUUUUUUUUUCCUGUUCCCCUGUCAGCUGGUCUGACAGAUUUAAGAACUCUCAUUCUUAAAAGACUUUGGACUUAAAUUCUAGCAUUUUAGACUAGGACUGUUCUACUGUGAAGAAAGUUCUGUCUCCUUUAGCCCGGUUUGUUUCUCCCUGCUCAGGUCUAGAAUCCCAAGCAGUGUUCUUUUCUGGUGAACACUGUGAGCCGCAGAUGUGACUUUUUUUUUAAAGUCAUCUCUUCAGCAAUCCAGAGGUUCCUUGACCUCAUUAUUUGUCCUAUCUCUCCCUUAUAGUCCUAAGCCAAGACAUUUGACCUUUGACAUUUGACCUUUGCAGUGUCAUGUGAGGGCGUCAGUAUAGAGGCCUUUGCAUCUGGGCCUGGCACCCGCUCUCUGCCUCUGGAGGCUAAACCCUGUCUGGAUUUCUCUUGGGAUCUAACGUGGGAUCUUCUGGACAGACAACCGUGACAUCAGCAGUGCUGGUGCUGCUGUGUGUGGACUGAACACCUGCACUUUGCAGAGGACACGCUGCAUGGGCCCCGCUUGCGGUUCAUUCAGGCCUGCUGCAGGAGCUCUGAGAACAAGAAAGAGUGGACACCCGUUCCCCUGCAUCAUCUGUCUUGCGUGCUAUUUCAGAGUGGGGAAGUGAUAAACUAUUUGCCUUCUGGAGCUCUUUGUGAAAAAUUAAAAAAAAACUUAGCUCAAA